AUGACCCCAACAUCAUGGGUAGGAGAUAAUUACAUUGAUCAAGAAGCUACAGUUUCCAUUUCCCUACUUGCCAGGGAGCAAAGGAAGUUCCAGUGGGCUGGGAGUAAGGGACAGAUUGUGGACCCUGACGAAAGGCGUGCUGGAGAAAGCUGGGAGCCCGCCGUUCGCACACAAAGCUGCGGAGUUCCCAAGCGGCGGGCGUUCUCGCCCCGGGGUACCGCAGCGCGCCAGGAAGCGCCCUGGGCUCUCUGGCUGUCCAGCCGCUCUGCUGGUGGCCGGGAGAAGUUAGUCACCCGGAGCCCGAAUCCGGCGAGCGUCAAAGCAUCAAGAGGCUGGAGAAUGGGGAGGGAGGAAACCGGGUGCCGGGACGGAGGGGAGGAAGCGAAGGGAACGCGGUGGUUAGGGGACGCACGGGAAGCUGAAAAGCUCUGGCUGGUGGAUGGAGUUGCACGGUCUGCGAGGCCAGAGCGCACGGGUGUGCAAAGGGGAAAAACUUGCGGCAGGAACUUCCCACCGAGGGCGAGAAAAGCAGGCAAGAAGGAGGCAGGGAGAGACUUGAAACGUCUCAAUAACUUUAACCAAAACACCCGUUCAGGAGAUGAGCGCUCGCGCUGCUCUCGGCGCUCGCAGCUGCCGACUGGGGAUGACGGCGGGCAGGAGGAGACCGCAGCCGAAGGGACACAGACACGCCGCUUCACCAGCUCGCCUCAGGCUGCCCCCCUGCAUUUUUGUUUUAAUUUUUACGGCUUUUUCCCCUCUCUUUCUUCCCUUCCUCCUGGUCCCAGCAGAGCCAAGGAAACCCACAAAAUAAGAAAGGAAGUGGGCCCCGGAGCUUGGAACCUCCACAGCCGGCUUGUCCAGCGCAGCGCGGGGGCGGGAGGCUGCGCGCACCAGUUGCCAGCCCGGUGCGCGGUACCUUUCCUUACUUUUCUUGAAACAGCGAUCGUGCCUGCAUUUGGUGGUUUUUUGGUUUUUGUUUUUUUCCUUUUCCCGUAUUUGCUGAAUCUCCACUAUCCGACUUUUUUUUUUUAA